AGUGGUGUGGUACCGGGUACCCGGAGACGUGUAUCGGACGGUGGGCCGCAGCCAUGGCCGAGAGAAAACCUAACGGUGGCAGCGGCGGCGCCUCCACUUCCUCAUCGGGCACUAACUUACUUUUCUCCUCCUCGGCCACGGAGUUCAGCUUCAAUGUGCCCUUCAUCCCAGUCACCCAGGCCUCCGCUUCUCCGGCCUCCCUGCUCUUACCGGGAGAGGAUUCCACAGAUGUUGGUGAGGAGGACAGCUUCCUUGGUCAGACUUCUAUUCACACAUCUGCCCCACAGACAUUUAGUUACUUCUCUCAGGUAUCAAGCAGCAGUGAUCCUUUUGGGAAUAUUGGACAGUCACCAUUAACAACUGCAGCAACCUCAGUUGGACAAUCAGGAUUCCCCAAGCCCCUGACUGCUCUCCCUUUUACAACUGGAUCCCAAGAUGUCUCGAAUGCAUUUUCACCAUCCAUUUCGAAGGCUCAACCUGGUGCUCCACCUUCCUCACUGAUGGGAAUAAAUUCUUAUCUGCCUUCUCAGCCAAGUAGUCUCCCUCCUUCAUAUUUUGGGAACCAACCCCAAGGAAUUCCCCAACCAGGAUACAAUCCAUAUCGCCAUACCCCUGGCAGCAGCAGGGCUAAUCCUUACAUUGCACCACCCCAGCUGCAGCAGUGCCAAACACCAGGCCCUCCUGCUCAUCCUCCACCUUCUGGACCCCCUGUUCAGAUGUACCAGAUGCCUCCAGGAUCUUUGCCACCGGUUCCUUCUUCAGUGCAGUCACCGGCACAGCAGCAGGUACCUGCCAGACCUGGGGCUCCCUCUGUUCAAGUGCCAUCUCCUUUUCUACUUCAAAACCAAUAUGAGCCUGUUCAGCCCCACUGGUUUUACUGCAAGGAGGUAGAAUACAAACAACUGUGGAUGCCUUUUAGUGUGUUCGACUCUUUGAAUCUUGAAGAAAUCUAUAAUUCAGUUCAGCCAGAUCCGGAGAGCGUGGUUCUUGGCACGGAUGGAGGGCGCUACGAUGUUUACCUCUAUGACCGAAUAAGGAAGGCUGCCUACUGGGAAGAGGAGCCAGCCGAAGUGAGACGCUGUACUUGGUUUUACAAGGGGGACACAGAUAGUCGAUUUAUUCCCUAUACUGAGGAGUUCAGUGAAAAACUAGAGGCUGAAUAUAAAAAAGCUGUAACCACUAAUCAGUGGCACCGAAGAUUAGAGUUUCCAAGUGGAGAGACAAUUGUUAUGCACAAUCCAAAGGUUAUUGUUCAGUUCCAGCCCUCCUCAGUGCCAGAUGAAUGGGGCACCACGCAAGAUGGACAGACAAGGCCCAGGGUUGUAAAGCGUGGAAUUGAUGAUAACCUUGAUGAAAUUCCCGACGGGGAGAUGCCUCAAGUUGACCAUUUGGUGUUUGUGGUGCAUGGCAUUGGACCUGUGUGUGACUUACGCUUUAGGAGCAUUAUUGAGUGUGUGGAUGAUUUUAGGGUGGUUUCUCUCAAAUUGCUGCGGACACAUUUCAAGAAAUCUUUAGAUGACGGGAAAGUAAGCAGAGUGGAGUUCCUUCCAGUUCAUUGGCAUAGUUCUUUGGGUGGGGACGCCACAGGUGUGGACAGGAAUAUUAAGAAAAUCACUUUGCCAAGUAUUGGUCGAUUUCGUCACUUUACCAAUGAAACUUUGCUAGAUAUUUUAUUUUAUAACAGCCCCACCUACUGUCAGACAAUUGUGGAAAAAGUAGGAAUGGAGAUAAACCAUCUGCAUGCACUCUUUAUGAGUCGGAACCCAGACUUCAAAGGAGGUGUCUCUGUUGCUGGUCACAGUUUAGGUUCUUUAAUAUUGUUUGACAUCCUGUCUAAUCAAAAAGAUUUGAAUUUAUCAAAGUGCCCUGGACCUCUUGCUGUUGCUAAUGGAGUUGUGAAGCAGCUACAUUUUCAGGAAAAGCAGAUGCCUGAAGAGCCAAAGCUGACUUUGGAUGAGUCGUAUGACCUUGUUGUUGAAAAUAAAGAAGUCCUAACUUUGCAAGAAACUCUGGAAGCACUUAGCCUCUCUGAAUAUUUUAGCACUUUUGAAAAGGAAAAGAUUGAUAUGGAGUCCCUGCUUAUGUGUACAGUUGAUGACCUGAAGGAAAUGGGGAUACCCCUUGGACCCAGAAAGAAGAUAGCUAACUUUGUAGAACAUAAAGCAGCCAAACUGAAAAAAGCAGCGUCAGAAAAGAAGGCAGUGGCGGCCACUUCUACAAAAGGACAAGAGCAAAGUGCCCAGAAGACUAAAGACAUGGCUUCCCUCCCCUCAGAAUCCAAUGAGCCAAAGAGGAAACUUCCAGUUGGUGCUUGCGUGUCUUCUGUGUGUGUGAAUUAUGAAUCUUUUGAAGUUGGCGCCGGACAGGUUUCUGUUGCUUACAACUCAUUAGAUUUUGAACCAGAGAUAUUCUUUGCCUUGGGGUCUCCAAUUGCUAUGUUUCUCACUAUUCGAGGAGUUGAUAGGAUAGAUGAGAAUUACAGCCUUCCUACCUGUAAAGGGUUCUUCAAUAUUUAUCAUCCGCUUGAUCCAGUGGCAUAUAGAUUAGAACCUAUGAUUGUUCCAGAUUUGGACCUAAAAGCUGUUCUCAUUCCACAUCACAAAGGCAGAAAAAGACUUCAUUUAGAAUUGAAAGAGAGUCUCUCUCGUAUGGGAUCUGAUUUGAAGCAGGGUUUUAUUAGCUCUCUCAAAAGUGCUUGGCAGACAUUAAAUGAGUUUGCCCGUGCUCAUACGUCUUCAACCCAGUUGCAAGAAGAAUUGGAGAAGGUGGCCAAUCAGAUCAAAGAAGAAGAAGAAAAGCAAGUAGUUGAAGCAGAAAAGGUUGUUGAAAGUCCAGAUUUUUCCAAGGAUGAGGACUACUUAGGAAAGGUUGGAAUGUUAAAUGGAGGCCGCCGAAUUGACUACGUUCUCCAAGAAAAACCAAUAGAGAGUUUUAAUGAAUACCUUUUCGCUCUUCAGAGUCACUUAUGCUAUUGGGAAUCUGAAGAUACUGCUCUGUUACUACUUAAAGAAAUUUAUCGAACAAUGAACAUUAGUCCAGAACAGCCCCAGCAUUGAUCAAACUUCAGUUUUACUGUACUUUCUUGUCUGCACAGAAAGUCCCAGUACAACUUCCAUUGCUGAGAAAAUCCUCAGAGGACUUUCCCACUUCGCUCCUGUGAUGGAUGACAGAAGAGUGAUUCAUUAACAAUUGCUCAGCCACAAUUCUCGGAUAUAGGGAUUCAAAAGACAGGACACAGAACUAACACAGUGAAAAAAAUCAGUACCACAUUUGGACAGUAUAGGUGAGAAAACAUAAUUAUAAAAAUGAUGCCAUGAAAAAUUCCACAGAUCAGUUUAGUUGUAUAGUUGUCAAAGUUAUAUGUGAUAUCAAUGAAGAAAUAUUUGUAGCAUGUAAACGGUUAUUUCUGUUUCUUAAAAAGUAUUGUUAGUGGGCUAUUAAACUUGGAUUUUUCUUUUUAUUAAUGCAGUAUGUUCUUUUUAUUCAAGUAUGAACUUGUUGAGAAACUAUAGUAAUAUGAUUUUUAAGAGAUUUAUGUUCUACUUAAAAUGUGAAUUGUACUUCUGAGCUGCCUUAAUGCAAGGUCAUUUAUAUUUGUUAAGAGGAAAUAAUCAAGAUCACUCAUAUCCCAACUGAAUCUGAGGUUUUAUAAAUCCCUCAAACGAUUGCUGAGAGCCUGAUUGUGGAAAGAAGUGAGAUGCACCUUAUUUUCAAGAAGUCCUGGGAAGCGCUCUCCUAGCACGUCCAUUUCCAGGAGGAGAAGCAAGCAGAUGAGAGGUUUUCCAUUUUGUCAUCCAAGGUAGCUGUGCACUUGCCUUGUUGCUGAAGUUCCAAUAAUGUGAAAACCAAAGUAGAGGUUUUUUUCUUCUUCUUUUUGUUUUCUAUUAAUUUCACUUAUACCAAAGUGUUUGAAAGUAUGAAAUGUGUUGCUUCUGAGUUAUAUAAGGCUACUUCAUGACAAGACUGCUUUGUAAUAUUUCACUUUGUUUUACUACAAAUUCAGAUCACUUUGUUUUACUAUAAAUUCAGAUUAUCCAAAUAUUUUCCUAAUACUAUGUGGGAAUGCUGAUUUUCUUUUGUUACGUAGUGGAAACAUUUUGCAUUGUUUACAUAGUUCUCAUGGAACAUGGAAAUUUUUGAAAGUGAUAUAUGAUACACAUUUUUUGUGUAUGUAUUCUAAUUAGUGUGAAUAAAGCAGUAACAUUAAUGCAUUUUUUAAGCAGCAAACUUAUGUAUUUCUCUUGUCUUCCUUAAAAGUGUCCCCAUGAACUCAGUGUUUAUUCCCUUUUCAUUUUGAGUACCUGCUUAUAUGGUCAGUAUGUAACGUUAGCAUUGGCUCCUAAUGGUAGAAUUAGAACAGCAAGAUUGUAGAGCUGUAAUUGACUCCAGACAACAUAGAUUUCAGCCACCUCAUUCUACAGCUGAGGCCAGGACAAUAAAUGCCUUUCCCAGACUGGGUAGUGGCAGAUCUGGGAUGGAAUAUGGUUUUCUUGAUUCCCUUUCAGCCUUCAUUUCUCUCUCUCAGGACUACUACUUUUUAAUUACUUUUCACUUAAUUUCCCAAUACUGAUGAAAUAAAGAAAAAUGAGGGUUAUUUAUAUACAUUUCAAUAAAAUCCAAUUUGAUUUUUCAACUUACAUCUGAUUUUUGUUUGUGUCAUUCAGCCUGUCUUCUGAGUAAUGGGCAGAGAAGGACCAGGGUUCGUAGAAGAAGCAUGUGGCAGCUGAGUGGCAGCAGUCUUGCCCUUUCAUUUUAAUACUUGAGUACACAGAAAAUAGAAUUUUUGAGUGACUCUGCCUGUGGAUAUAUAUACUCAUACAUACAUAUAUAUAUAUACACACACACAUAUGUAUGUAUGUAUGUAUUACUAUUCAGUCUCUUAAAAACCAAAAAACAGUAGAUCCCCUGAGGGUAGAGUCUUUAUGUAUGAACAUAUUGUUCACUGUUGUAACCACCUUGCAGGAUUUCAGUCUAUAAACUAGGUGAGAAUCCAGCUGCUGAGUGAAGCUUGAUCUCUGCCUCUUCCUCAGGAGCAGCUCAUCCCCUGACAACCUCCCCUCCCAGCCCCUAAUCUGGUUUAAUGCCCUCCUUUUCCCCAGAUAAAGAAAGUCAUGUCUGUAGUUAUUCCAAAAGUGUUUCAUGUGUAGAGUUUGGCACAAAAAGUAAAAAGCGCCAGCAUCUGAAGUCAAAGGUGAAAGAGUCAUCACAGUACUGAUGAAGACACCCAGGCCUCGUCAGCUAUGUUAACGUGCUGUAUGACAAGAGGAACCUGCUUUCUAAGUCUGCUGGACACGCGUGCUUCUUGAAUCCAACCAGACAAGCAUGUUUUCUCAAAACCACAGUAUAAGACAAGGAAACUGCACAGAUUCGAGUGAUUUUUGAGGUAAGUAUGUUAUUGGAAAGGUGUGAUCUAUAUAGAACCCUGUACAUGAAAAGGAGGAGAUGCCGCUAUCUUGGCAGGGAUGAUCAUGUAUUUGAAAUAGUAACUCACAGCAUUUGGUCUCAUGAUAAGAGUACUGAAGAUUAUCCCAGAAAACCUAGGAUGAUUGGUAUUUAUAGUACCAUUGUUUCAGGUUUUUAUGACUUGAGGCAUCUAACUAUCUUAAUGCUGUACUUUAGUGUUUACCAAGCAGCUUUCUGGUGGAAACUUGAACUGCAGACACUGAGUGUUUUGGUUUUCCUCCAAGUUAUAGUUCUCAUUGUAACUUAAUAAGUUGGCAUUCCAGCUUAGUUUGAGUCAGUUUCCCAGGGCUGGGUCCUCAGAGGAGAGUGGAUAGAAUUCAGUUCCUCUAUGAGCUGGGGUGCUGACAUUGUGUUCCUGCUGUUGACUGUCCCUGCGGUGCACGGGACAGACUGUCAGCUAACCUGUCUUCAUGACAUUUCUAUAAUACUCCUCAGGGGGUUAACCCCAUCUCUACUAAAAAUAAAAAAAAUUAGCUGGGCAUGGUGGCAUGUGCCUGUAGUCCCAGCUACAGGAGGCUGAGGCAGGAGAAUUGCUUGAACCCAGGAGGUGGAGGUUGCAGUGAGUUGGGAUCUCGCCACUGCACUCUAGCCUGAGUGACAGAGCGAGACUCUGUCUCAAAAAAAAAUAAAUGAAUAAAAAAUAAAACAGCAACUCUUGCAGAUUUCCCGAAUGUAUUGGUCCCAGAGAACACUGAAAAUAAUGUCAUGUUGUUAACACCAGUGGGAGUUUGGGAAAUAAUUCCAGCUCUUUAAUACUUCUUUCAGCUUCAGAUUAAGUGAAAUGAGUUUCACAUAUUUCAAUAUAUGAAAUUUUAUGAUGACACAUAAAACAGGCCAGGGGUUAUUGAGGACACAUCUGUGAGAUAGUGGGCAAUGCUACAUAUUCGUUAGUGGAUGUGCUGCAGUUCAGGUUCAUGGACAGGUGGGACUGGUGUGGUUGGGAUAACCCACCAUGUUUGUCUUUCAUUUCUUGUAUAAAGAGUGGUUUUUAAAAGACCUUACUAUGGAAUUUUCACAAAUACUCAAAAGUAUGGAGAAUGGUACAGUGAAUCCCCAUGUGCCCUUUUCCCAGCUUCAGGGGUGGUGUCAGUGAUAAUGAUUUGGCUCUGUGUCCCCACCCAAAUCUCAUCUUGAAUUGUAAUCCCCACGUGUCAGGGGAGGGACCUGGUGGGAGGUGAUUGGAUCAUGGGGGCUGUUUCCCCAUGCUGUUCUUGUGAUAGUGAGGGAGUUCUCACAAGAUCUGAUGGUUUUAAAAGUGGCAGUUUUCCCUGCACUCUCUCCUGCCACCUUGUGAAGAAGGUGCCUGCUUCCCCUUUGCCUUUCGUCACAAUUGUAAGUUCCCCGAGGUUCGUCAUGAUUGUAAGUUUCCUGAGGUCUCCCCAACCAUGCAGAACUGUGAGUCACUUGAACCCCUUUUGUUUAUAAAUUGCCCAGUCUCAGGUAGUACCUUGAUAGCAGUGUGAAAAUGGACUAAUACAGUCAGGGACCUAAAAGACAGGUAAAGAGAUGUGGCCAGGUGAAGACGGAAAAAGGACAGUGCAUUCCAGACCUGUGGAAAGACGCGAGGUUGGAAAGAACAUCACAACUGGGGCGACUGAAGAAAUUAUGUUGUUAAGCACGAAAUGCAGAGAGAGAGCUAUGUGAAUGUGUUGAGUGUGAUUUUCAUUAAACAAUUUUUAAAGAAA